GUCUUUGGCUGCCGCUGGAACUCCGGGUCUCGUCUUCACUGCUCUGUGUCCUCUGCUCCUAGAGGCCCAGCCUCUGGUCCUGUGACCUGCAGGUAUUGGGAAUCCACAGCUAAGACGCCGGGACACCCUGGAAGCCUAGAAAUGGACGACCUGAGGUAUGGAGUGUAUCCUGUCAAGGGGGCAAGUGGAUACCCUGGGGCUGAGAGGAAUCUUCUGGAGUACUCUUAUUUUGAAAAGGGGCCGUUGACAUUUAGGGAUGUGGUCAUAGAAUUCUCUCAGGAGGAGUGGCAAUGCCUGGACACUGCUCAGCAAGAUUUGUAUAGGAAAGUGAUGUUAGAGAACUUCAGAAACCUGGUGUUCUUGGGUAUUGAUGUCUCUAAGCCAGAUCUGAUCACCUGUCUGGAGCAAGGAAAAGAUCCCUGGAAUAUGAAGAGACACAGUAUGGUAGCCACACCCCCAGUUACAUAUUCUCAUUUUGCCCAGGACCUUUGGCCACAGCCGGGCAUAAAAGAUUCUUUCCAAAAAGUGAUACUGAGAGAAUAUGGAAAUUAUGGACAUAAAGAUUUACAGUUAAGAAAAGGCUGUAAAAGUGUGAAUGAGUGUAAUGUGCAAAAAGAAGGUUAUAAUGAACUAAAAGAGUAUUUGACAACUACCCAGAGCAAAAUAUUUCAAUGUGAUAAAUAUGUGAAAGUCUUUCAUAAAUUUUUAAAUUCAAAUACACAUAAGACAAGACAUACUGGAAAGAAACCUUUCAAAUGUAAAAAAUGUGGCAAAUCAUUUUGCAUGCUUUUACACCUAGGUCAACAUAAAAUAAUUCAUAUUAGAGAGAAUUCUUACCAAUGUGAAGAAUGUGGCAAAGCCUUUAAAUGGUUCUCAACCCUUACUAGACACAAGAGAAUUCAUACUGGAGACAAAUCCUACAAACAUGAAGAAUGUGGAAAAGGUUUUAACCACUCCACAACUCUUACUAGACAUAAGGUAAUUCAUGCUGGAGAGAAACACUACAAAUGUGAAAAAUGUGGCAAAGAUUUUAAACAGUCCUCACACCUUACUAAACAUAAGACAAUUCAUGCUGGAGAGAAACCCUACAAAUGUGAAGGAUGUGGCAAAGCUUUCUGCCAAUUCUCAUACCUUACUAAACAUAAGAUAAUUCAUACUGGAGAGAAACCCUACAAAUGUGAGGAAUGUGGCAAAGCUUUUAAUUGGUACUCACACCUUACCAGACAUAAGAUAAUUCAUACUGGAGAGAAACCCUACAAAUGUGAAUAAUGUGGCAAAGCCUUUAAUGUAUUCGCAACCCUUACUAGACAUAAGAUAAUUCAUACUGAAGAGAAACCCUACAAAUGUGAGGAAUGUGGCAAAGCUUUUAAACAGUCCUCAAACCUUACUACUCAUGAAAAUUCAUUCUGGAGAGAAACCCUACAAAUGUGGAGAAUGUGGCAAAGCUUUCUUCAGAUUCUCAUACCUUACUACACAUAAGAUAAUUCAUACUGGAGAGAAACCCUACAAAUGUGAAGAAUGUGGCAAAGCUUUUAACUGUUACUCCUACCUUACUGCACAUAAGUUGAUUCAUACUGGAGAGAAACCCUACAAAUGUGAAGAAUGUGGCAAAGCUUUCUACCGAUUCAUUUACCUUACUACACAUAAGAGAAUUCACACUGGAGAGAAACCCUACAAAUGUGAAGAAUGUGGCAAAGCUUUCUACCGAUUAUCUUAUCUUACUACACAUAAGAUGAUUCAUACUGUAGAGAAACGCUACAAAUGUGAGGAAUGUGGCAAAGCUUUUAACUGGUACUCACGCCUUACUACACAUAAGAGAAUUCAUACUGGUGAGAAACCCUACAAAUGUGAAGAAUGUGGCAAAGCCUUUAGUGUAUUCUCAACCCUUACUAAACAUAAGAUAAUUCAUACUGGAGAGAGACCCUACAAGUGUGAAGAAUGUGGCAAAGCCUUUAAUGUAUUCUCAACCCUUACUAAACAUAAGAGAAUUCAUAAUGGAGAGAAACCCUACAAAUGUUUAGAAUGUGGCAAAGAUUUCUACCAAUUCUCAUACCUUACUACACAUAAGAUGAUUCAUACUGGAGAGAGACCCUACAAACAUGAAGAAAGUGGCAAAGCUUUUAACUGUUCCUCACAAAUUACUAGACAUAAGAUAAUUCAUACUGGAGAGAAACCCUACAAAUGUGAAGAAUGUGGCAAAGCUUUUUAAAAAUCCUCAAACCUUACUAAUCAUAAGAUAACUCAUACUGGAGAGAAACCCUACAAAUGUGAAGAAUGUGGAAAAGCUUUUAACCAGUCCUCAACUCUUACUAGACAUAAGAGAGUUCAUACUGGAGAGAAACCCUACAAAUGUGAAGAAUGUGGCAAAGCUUAUAACUGGUCCUCAAACCUUACUAAACAUAAGAAAAUUCAUACUGGAGAGACACCCUACAAAUGUGAAGAAUGUGGCAAAGCUUUUAACCAAUCUUCAACCCUUACUAUACAUAAGAUAAUUCAUAUUGGAGAAUAACACUACAAAUGUAAAAAAUGUGGCAAACCUUAUAACCAGUACUCAUACUUUACUACACAUAGGAGAAUUCAUGCGGAAGAGAAUUUCUACAAAUGUGAAGAAUGUGGCAAAGGCUUUGACUGGUCCUCUACCCUUACUAAAGAUAAAAGAGUUUGACUGGGUGCGGUGGCUCAUGCCUGUAAUCCCAGCACUUUGGGAGGCUGAGGCAGGCAGAUCACCUGGUCAAUGGUCCUCUACCCUUACUAAAGAUAAAAGAGUUUGACUGGGUGCGGUGGCUCAUGCCUGUAAUCCCAGCACUUUGGGAGGCUGAGGCAGGCAGAUCACCUGGUCAAGAGUUCAAGACCAGCCUGGCCCAUAUGGUGAAACCCCAUCUCUACUAAAAAUAUAAAAAAUUAGCCAGGUGUAGUGGUGCACACCUGUAGUCCCAGCUACUCUGGAGGCCUAGGUGGGAGAAUCGCUUGAACCCAGGAGGUGGAGGUUGCAGUGAGCUGAGAUGGCUCCACUGCACUCCAGCCUGGAUGACAGAGAGAGACUCUAUCUCCAAAAAAAUAAAUAAAUAAAUAAAAAAAAUAAGAGAGUUCAUACUAGAGAGAAACCCUGCAAAUGUGAAGAAUGUGAGAAAGCUCUUAACCAGUCCUCACACCUUACUGCACAUAAGAGAAAUCAUACUGGAAGGAAACCCUACAAAUGUAAAGAAUGUGAGAAAGCUUUUAACUGGUACUCAUGCCUUACUGCACAUAAGAUAAUUCAUACUGGAGAGAAACUCUACAAAUGUCAAGAAUGUGGCAAAGCUUUUAACCGGUACUCAACCCUUACUACACAUAAGGUAAUUCAUGCUGGAGAGAUACCCUACAAAUGUGAAGAAUGUGGCAAAGGUUUUUAUUGAUUCUCAUACUUUACUAAAAAUAAGGUGAUUCAUUCUGGAGAGAAAUUCUACAAAUGUGAAGAAUGUGGCAAAGGCUUUAAUUUGUCCUCAACACUUACUAAACAGAAUUCAUAGCAGAGAGAAAUCCUACAAAUAUGAAGAAUGUCACAAAGCUUUUAACCACUUCUCAACCCUGAUGACACAUAAGGUAAUUCGUGCUGGAGAGAAACCCUACAAAUAUGAAGAAUAUCUCAAAACUUUUUAUAGAUUCUCAUACCUUAUUAAACAUAAAAUCUUACAGGAGAGAAAUUAUACAAAUGUGAAGAAUGUGGCAAAGCUUUUAAGAAAUCCUCAUCCAUUACUAAACAAGAUAAUUUGUACUGGAGAGAAAACCUACAAACGUGAGGAAUGUGGCAAAGCCUUUAAUGGUCCCCUCAACUUUCUGCACAUAAGAUAAUUUAUACUGUGGAGAAGCCUUACAAAUGUGAAAAAUGUAGCAAACCUUUUAACUAAUCCUCAACCCUUACUACACAUAAGAUAAUUAAUGCUGGAGGGAAAUCCCACCCAUGUGGCAAAGCUUUUAAUCAAUCCUCAAACCUUACUAAACAUAAGAUAACUCAUACUGGAGAAAAAUCUUAGAAAUGUGAAGGAUGUGGUAAAGCCGUUAUCCAGUCCUCAACUCCCACUAAACAUAACAUAAUUCAUACUGGAGAGAAACCUCACAACUGUGAAGAAUGUGGCAAAGCUUUUAACCAGUCCUACAAACCUUUUUGAACAAAAUAAUUCAUACAGGAGAGAAACACUACAAAUGUGAGGAAUGUGACAAAGCCUUUAACCAGUCCUCAAUUCUUACCAAACAUAAGAAAAUUCAUAUUGGAGAUUAACCUUAUGAGUGUGAAAAAUAUGGCAAAAGCUUUAACUAGUUCUCAGUUAUUAUUAUUAUUUUUAGAGAUGGAGUUUCACUCUUGUUGCCAAGGCUGCAAUACUGUGGCAUGAUUUCAGCUCACUGCAACCUCCGUCUCCCAGGUUUAAGCAAUUCUGCCUCAGCCUCCCGAGUAGCUGGGAUUACAGGCAUGCACCACUAUACCCAUCUAAUUUUGUAUGUUUAGCAGAGAUGGGGUUUCUCCAUGUAGAUCAGGCUGGUCUUGAACUCCUGACCUUGUAAUCUGCCCACCUCAGCCUCCCAAAGUGCUGGGAUUACAGGCAUGAGCCACCACGCUCAGCCACUAGUCCUCAGAUCUUAACACACAUAAGAUAAUUCAUACUGGAAAGAAACUCCACAAACCAGAAAGAUGCAAUAAUGCUUUUGACAACACCUCAAGCUUUUCUAACCAUAAAAAGAAUCAUAUUGGUGAGAAAUCCUAGAAAUGUGAAGAAUGUGACAAAGUCUUUAAAUGGUUGUCAUACUUGACUUUUUUCUUUUUUUGAGAUGAAGUCUCACUCUUGUCCCCCAGGCUGGUGUGCAAUGGCAUGAUGUCGGCUCACUGCAAACUCCGCCUCCCAGGUUCAAGUGAUUCUCCUACCUCAGCCUCCCAAGUAGCUGGGAUUACAGGCACCUGCCACCACGCCUGGCUAAUUUUUGUACUUUUAGUAGAGAUGGGGUAUGACCAUCUUGGCCAGGCUGGUCUCAAACUCCUGACCUCAGGUGAUCCGCCCACCUCGGGCCUCCCAAAGUGCUGGGAUUACAGGCAUGAGCCACCACUCCCUGCCUUACUUGAUUACAUUCAAUAUAAUUCAUACUGGAAAGAAAUCCUACAAGUGAGAGCAAUGUGGCAAAACUUAACCACCUUAUUGCACAGAAAAGCAUUUAUGUUUGAGAAAAAUUAUACAAAUACAGACUGUGAAAAAGACAUUAAUAUCUGCUUACAUCUUAACACCAGAGAGUUCAUACUUAAUAAAAGCAAGAUAAGGGCAAUUACUGUCAAAAGGUCUUUCAGAAAAAUAUAACCCUUUAAAGUGAAGAAGAGAAUUUAUAUUGAAGAUGGACAUUACAAACAUAAAGAGGGUUGUAGUACCUUUACUUGAAUCAAAUUUUAUUGUACACAUUUUGUACUAGAGGAAAACUCUGAAGCAGUUGCUCAAGCUUUGUUCAACAUUAGGGCACUUAUAUUGGAAAAGUGUCUUGCAGAUAUAAUAAAUGUGGAAAAACACUUUUUCAAAAACUACAUCAGAAAACACCAGAGUUUAUACUGAAGAAUAUUUUUGAAGAUGCACUAAAAAUGAAAAAAUAUUUAAUCCAAAUUAGGGCUAUGUAAAUAUCAGAAUUUAUAAUAGAAAUAUAUAAGGAACUGACACUGCAGAUAUACUAAGUCAAGAGUUCUGAGUAUAGAAAAUAAUCUAAAACUAAAGUUGAUAGAAAAAGUAUUUGUAUAUAAAUUUAAGAGGAGUAAAAGAUUUUUUGCAGAGUAAUAACUACAUUCUAAGUAUACUUUAUUUCUUGAAAAAAUUACAGACUUUGAAAGCAAAUGAUGUAAUUCAACACUCAUUUUCUGGUGUUUCUUCAUUCUUAUUCACUUGUGAAAGCAUGUGAUAAUUGUUGCAUCAAAGGUAUGAGAGAUUCUUUUCCAUUAGGUGGGCAUUUAUGAUCUUUUCUAUGGACAAGUAAGGACAUUAGAAUGUAAGAUGCAUGAUGAAAAAGUGGAGAGGUUCUUUGUGGUUAACUUAUACUCUUGAGUGAUAUAUGAGGUAGGUGUUAAGAGUAUUGUUCUUUUGCAUUAUGAGAAAACUAGUAGUAUAUUAUUAGUAUAUUAUUGUACUAAUUGUACUUUUAUAUAAUAAAAUGCAGCACAUUUUUAAAAUUUUA